CGGCGCUGCCUCUGGAUUGCCUGCGUGUGGGAGUACAACUCUGCCUCUCCAAGGAGAACGGGUUGUGACCACUGAACAAAACUUGCCCAUUGAAAGCAAACCCGGAACAGCUGGAUAAUGUCCACCCCGAGCCGAUUCAAGAAGGACAAAGAGAUCAUAGCCGAGUAUGAAAGUCAAGUCAAAGAAAUUCGAGCUCAACUGGUAGAACAACAAAAAUGCCUGGAGCAGCAAACGGAGAUGCGAGUUCAGCUUCUCCAGGAUCUGCAAGAUUUCUUCCGAAAAAAAGCUGAAAUUGAGACGGAAUAUUCCCGGAAUCUAGAGAAGUUAGCAGAAAGGUUCAUGGCAAAAACAAGAAGCACUAAGGAUCAUCAACAAUACAAGAAAGACCAGAACCUGUUGUCUCCAGUGAACUGCUGGUAUUUGCUCCUGAACCAAGUAAGGAGAGAAAGCAAAGACCAUGCAACCUUGAGUGACAUCUAUCUGAACAAUGUGAUUAUGCGGUUCAUGCAGAUAAGUGAGGAUUCUACCAGGAUGUUUAAAAAGAGCAAAGAGAUUGCAUUCCAACUUCAUGAGGAUUUAAUGAAGGUUCUUAAUGAGCUUUAUACGGUGAUGAAAACAUACCAUAUGUAUCAUGCAGAGAGCAUCAGUGCAGAGAGCAAGCUGAAAGAGGCCGAAAAACAAGAGGAAAAGCAAAUUGGGAGAUCUGGUGAUCCAGUCUUCCAUAUUCGACUAGAGGAGAGACAUCAACGGCGAAGCUCUGUAAAGAAAAUUGAAAAAAUGAAAGAAAAAAGACAAGCAAAAUAUUCAGAAAAUAAGCUAAAAUCAAUUAAGGCACGGAACGAAUAUCUCCUAACACUUGAAGCCACCAAUGCCUCAGUUUUCAAGUACUAUAUUCAUGAUCUUUCUGAUUUAAUUGAUUGCUGUGAUCUUGGCUACCAUGCAAGUCUGAACAGAGCCCUAAGAACAUAUCUGUCUGCGGAGUACAACCUUGAAACCUCCAGACAUGAGGGCUUAGACAUUAUUGAGAAUGCAGUUGAUAAUUUAGAGCCCAGGAGCGAUAAGCAGAGAUUCAUGGAGAUGUACCCUGCUGCGUUCUGUCCACCAAUGAAGUUUGAGUUUCAGUCUCACAUGGGUGAUGAGGUGUGCCAGGUCAGUGCCCAGCAGCCAGUCCAGGCAGAGCUCAUGCUCAGGUACCAACAGUUGCAGUCCCGCCUUGCCACGCUCAAAAUCGAGAAUGAAGAGGUUAAGAAAACGACUGAAGCCACCUUGCAGACGAUACAAGAUAUGGUCACCAUCGAGGACUAUGAUGUUUCUGAAUGCUUCCAGCACAGUCGUUCCACAGAAUCAGUGAAGUCCACUGUCUCUGAAACCUACCUGAGUAAACCCAGCAUCGCCAAGAGAAGAGCCAACCAGCAGGAAACUGAACAGUUCUACUUCAUGAAACUCAGAGAAUAUUUGGAAGGCAGUAAUCUCAUCACAAAACUUCAAGCCAAACAUGACUUGCUGCAGAGGACCCUGGGAGAAGGUCAUAGAGCUGAAUAUAUGACUACAAGGCCUCCAAAUGUUCCCCCUAAGCCCCAGAAACACAGGAAGUCCAGGCCCCGCUCACAGUAUAAUACUAAGUUGUUUAAUGGGGAUUUGGAAACAUUCGUCAAGGACUCAGGACAGGUUAUUCCCCUCAUUGUGGAAAGCUGUAUUCGGUUCAUCAAUCUCUAUGGUCUUCAGCAUCAGGGGAUUUUCAGAGUGUCUGGUUCCCAGGUGGAAGUCAAUGAUAUUAAAAAUUCAUUUGAGAGAGGUGAAAAUCCUUUGGCUGAUGACCAGAGUAACCAUGAUAUUAACUCAGUUGCUGGCGUUCUGAAGCUCUAUUUCCGUGGGCUGGAAAACCCCCUCUUUCCUAAGGAAAGAUUUAACGAUCUGAUUUCUUGUAUCAGAAUAGAUAAUCUCUAUGAGAGGGCGCUUCACAUCCGCAAACUCCUCCUGACUUUGCCCAGGUCGGUCCUUAUAGUGAUGAGGUACCUCUUUGCCUUCCUCAAUCAUCUAUCACAGUACAGCGAUGAGAAUAUGAUGGACCCUUAUAACCUGGCCAUUUGCUUUGGCCCAACAUUGAUGCCUGUCCCAGAAAUACAGGAUCAAGUGUCUUGCCAGGCACAUGUGAAUGAAAUUAUCAAAACCAUCAUCAUCCACCAUGAGACUAUUUUCCCAGAUGCUAAAGAGCUGGAUGGCCCUGUUUAUGAGAAAUGUAUGGCUGGAGAUGACUAUUGCGACAGCCCAUACAGUGAGCACGGUACAUUGGAGGAAGUGGACCAAGAUGCUGGUACAGAGCCCCACACAAGUGAAGAUGAAUGUGAGCCAAUAGAAGCAAUAGCCAAGUUUGACUAUGUUGGGCGGUCUGCCAGAGAACUAUCCUUCAAGAAGGGUGCCUCCCUGCUGCUGUAUCACCGUGCAUCUGAGGACUGGUGGGAAGGCAGGCACAACGGGAUUGACGGGCUGGUGCCUCACCAGUAUAUAGUGGUGCAGGAUAUGGAUGAUACGUUUUCAGACACUCUGAGCCAAAAAGCCGACAGUGAGGCCAGCAGUGGGCCAGUCACGGAAGACAAGUCCUCAUCCAAGGACAUGAACUCCCCGACAGACCGUCAUCCUGACGGCUAUUUAGCCAGGCAACGAAAAAGAGGAGAGCCACCCCCUCCAGUAAGGCGUCCUGGCAGGACCAGUGAUGGCCAUUGCCCGCUCCACCCUCCACAUGCCCUUUCUAACUCCUCAGUUGACCUAGGGUCCCCAAGCCUUGCCAGUCACCCCCGGGGCCUGCUGCAGAACCGUGGCCUCAACAAUGACAGUCCUGAGCGGAGGCGCAGGCCUGGCCAUGGCAGCCUGACCAACAUCAGCCGGCACGACUCCCUCAAGAAGAUCGACAGCCCUCCCAUUAGAAGGUCCACGUCAUCAGGGCAAUACACGGGCUUCAAUGACCACAAGCCACUGGACCCAGAGACAAUUGCUCAGGAUAUUGAAGAAACGAUGAACACAGCUUUGAAUGAACUCCGAGAACUGGAGAGACAGAGCACAGCAAAGCAUGCCCCUGAUGUGGUGCUGGAUACCCUGGAGCAAGUGAAAAACUCUCCCACCCCUGCCACUUCCACGGAAUCUCUCAGCCCUUUGCACAACGUUGCCCUCAGGAGCUCCGAGCCUCAGAUUCGACGUAGCACGAGCUCCUCCAGUGACACAAUGAGUACUUUCAAGCCUAUGGUGGCACCCAGAAUGGGCGUGCAGCUGAAGCCUCCAGCCCUUAGGCCAAAACCUGCUGUUCUUCCAAAAACAAAUCCUACCAUAGGACCUGCCCCACCUCCCCAGGGUCCAACAGACAAGUCAUGCACAAUGUAAAAACCAGCCAAGCAAGGCCAUAAAGGGAGGUGACUUAAAAAAGAAAAUGGAUUAGUGACAAAAGUCACUGAUCCAUAACUUUCCUUAGUUUUGUGCUUAUAACUGGAGAUCUUUUGGCUUUUCUAUGUUGUCGAAUGUAAUGUCUGAGACUAGCUAAAUUAACACGGGCAUUUGUAUUUUGUAAUUUUUUUAAAUAACUGGACAUAUGUCAUUUUAAGGACAAUAGAAACACUUAGACUUACUUGAAAAUCCAAUGCUGCACCACUUGUAAUGAAGGCAACACCGCUCUCCACAUUGUACAGAGCUUCAGGUUUAAUGUAGCCCAGCUGAGUCAGAAAGGUUGUGACCUGAAGGCAGAAGAACCCGAAUGCCACACCUCAUUGGAGUAUAGCCAGUGUUGGUCUGUGGCACUUGGGCUGAAAGGUGAUAAUGGCAUUGCGUGGUAGCUGACAAUGAGCACCUUCGGUUCCAUGUGGAGCGGGGUUUAGCUCAUGCAAAAGACUUGCAAUUGUCUCCAUGGGACGAUCCCAGUGGGACUGUCAGCCCACAGCUCGAGUGGGUUGGAUGCUUGCCUCUUUCCUAACAGUUAUUUCCCCGGGUCCAGCUUAAAGACUCGAUGGAAGGAGGUAGAACCUCUGCUGUUACUGCUUGAACUUAACCUGGGAAAGGAGAGGAAGACACCAUCUCCAAAGCUAUUAAUGUCACUCCUUUUGCGAGCAUGAUUAGGCCCCGGAGAUUUCCAAGUCCCCCCAUCUACACUUACAAACGAUUAGAAGGGUUUAAUUUUAAAGACUUUCUGGUUACACUACUCCACGAACUCCUCCAAAGAUCCGUUAUUCAAUAACUGCCUAGAAAAUGUUUCCAUCUCCUCUAAAUCCCUGUGUUCUCCUCUGUGGAAAUGAAGGCAGCAAGAAGCACCUGAGGCCUUGGUUCAUGCAGUGUUCUCUUUUGACUAAAUCACCUAGGUUCCUUUAAACAUGCUACAAAGCCCAGGCAUGGUGGUGCACACCUGUACUCCCAGCUACUCGGGUGGUUUACACAGGAGGAUGGCUUUGGGCCUAGUAGUUCGAGUCCAGCCUGGGCAGCAUAGUGUGAGACCCUGUCUCUUAAAAAAAAAAAAAAUGCUACAAAGUCCUGAUGAUCCUAAAUUUGAAAUCCCAACUGUCCUCUCCAUUUGUCUUUGAGCCAACCCUGAACUGGCCCUGGUACCUGAGUAAGAGCCAUGCAGGGCCAUCAGCAGAACAUGGCCUUGUGGUUCUCACCCAGUUGUGUACCUCACAACCACAACUUCUUUUUCUUUGUCCCUUUUCCCCUUUUUGGUUUUGGUUUUGUAUGUGGGCUCUAUGUAACUCCCAUAGUCAGCUGAACUCUCAAUUGGAGACCCUCUUUCUCUGGCAUCCUAGCACACAGGCAAUUUUUUAAGCCUAUAUUUAUGCUACAUUUUCCCCCAUCUUAAGAAAAUUUGCUUUGAUUUCCAUUCUCCUACUAGCAGCAGCUGAUAUCACCUGUAGACCUAUGAGCAUUUUAUCUAUUCUAUCAUUGAAGUUACUGAUAAAGAUUUUUGUUGUUGUUGUUGUUGUUGGGAGAAAUGGAUUUCCCACAACUAAUCCCUCUGGCCCACCAUUAAUUUCCUUCUUGGUUUCAUUUCAAACUGGCAGCCAAUUGCACGCCCAUCUAAGAGCUACACAGUGUAGAUUUUACUUCAUCAGCCCAUUGGUGAAUGCAUCGUGCAGAAAAGAACUGGGAUCUGUACUAAAAUCAAGAUCAUUACUUUGAUCUCUACCUCAGUUUGCCAGUGUAGUCAUUCUAUUGCAGGAAGAGAUUAAAUUGAUGAGAUAUUGUUACUUUCAGAGUCACACUGCUGAUUGCUUGCCUGGGGCCUAAUUUCACAAAUGAAUAGUGACUUUUUUCCCAUGUAUUUCUAGGUAUGGUAAACUUUUAAACCUCCAAAUUUUCAGAGCCAUACUUUUUGCCCAUUUUGAAAAAGAAGCCCAGGACAGCACCUUGUCUAGCCCCUCCCCAUUUCUCCUGAGCUUUUGGGGUCCUUCAGCACCCUUGGACACCGUGGAGAUCCAGCCAAGACUGAGCUUUGAAUAGCACUAGCCCUUUUAAACAAUCCUCACAAAUUCCUUAGGAAUUUAAACUUUCCAAAAUAAUCCCCCACUUUUUUUUUUUUUUUUUUUUUUUUUUGAGUUGGAGUCUUGCUCUGUCGCCCAGGCCAGAGUACAGUGGUGCAAUCUCGGCUCCCUGCAACCUCCAUCUCCCGGGUUCAAGCAAUUCUCCUGAGUAGCUGGGAUUACAGGCGCCACCACCACGCCCAGCUAAUUUUUGUAUUUUUAGUAGAGAUGGGGUGUCACCAUGUUGGCCAGGCUGGUCUCAAACUCCUGACCUCAGGUGACCCACCAGCCUCAGCCUCCCAAAGUGCUGGGAUUACAGAUGUGAGCCACCAUGCCCGGCCAUUCCACCACUUCUUUAAAAUAGUAAGAAUUCUUAAAAACCAUAUUCCUUGUUUGAUGGAAGAGUAAGAUGUUAACAGAGGGCAUCAAAGGGCCAGAGGUGUCUUUGAAUUUAUUUUUUUUCAAUGUCUUUUCUGAGCUUCAGCCUUAGCUUUUCAGAUCUUCCUCCUACCUGUUCAUUUAUUCAGCCUUCUAUCUGGUCAUCCUCCCCAGCGGCUCCUCUCUCUGAUGUGUCCACCUACGGUGGAACGAGGAUUGCCUUUCUGUGCUCCCCAUCAGGACUUUGCUGUCUUGGCCGGCAGGAGUCGUGCUGCUGCAGAGCCUCACAGGCUGUGCCUUGUUUCAGGAAACAGCUCCUAAUACUCUCCCAUCACUCACUUUACCUGUCUCCAUCUUAUUUCCCUAUACUCCUAUUGUCAGCUUGAGACUUUUUUUUUUUUUCAAUUCCAAAUGAAGGGUAUGACCUCAGAGUGAGUGAGGACUCAGUAAAGACUCACCUCUCCUUACUUGGUUUAUUAAAUGUCUUCAGAUUCCAGAGAUAAGACAAGGUGGCCACUUCACAAAGAAUCCAGAAUCAUGCUCAGUAAAGCUCAUUAAAAGCCACUGCAGCUGAGAAGGUUCACAGCCCUUCUUUAUAGCCACAGAGGCAGCACACAGGGGAGGUGGGAAGACACAGGGAAACGAGAGAAGAAGGAUAAUGAGGCCUUGAGGUGUUCUGCCCCCAAUUUCAAGGAGCUUAUCAGGCUUCAUGUGCAAUUUGGGGAGGGGAGCUUUUUGAUGGUGGGUAAAUAAUGGCUCUACAAAGAUUACCUGACUCCACUGACACAAGAAUAUGUAUUCUCAGCUGAUAUAACUGUGUGUUCACAUCCCAUCCAUAGAACUCACUGAAGGAGAUUCAUCAAGUCAGCCUUUUGGACUGGGUUGGGGUUUGGGGAGUGGAUUUGGGGAUAGAGAGAAAGGUGUACUUAGUACACAUUUUCUAAUGGGCGUUACGUGAACUGUUUGAACCUGCUGAGUGGCGCUUUGUAGAGCUCCAUGUUCACGUUCAGUGUCAACACCAUUCAACAGCUUUGCACAUCUUCGUACAACAUAAUCUGGCUUUGGUGCCCCUUGAGCCACCUGUAGAAUAAUUUAUAGCAGGGUCCCACAAUCUACUGCAAUGAUCGUGAACAGUUAUCAGUGGAUAUAGUGCUCCAAGAGUCAAAUUGUAUCCGUUAAGGGUUUUCUAACUUUUGCUAUCCCCCCCGCGACCAAAAAAAGGGGGGGUUUAUAAUUUAAAGAAAAGGAAAAGAGGCGUGGGUUGGUAGUUGUGUCCUUAACAUUUAGGAAUGACAUAGCCUCUGGAGUCUACAAACUGAAGAAACUUUCAUCUGAUCAGCCUUGGAAAUCCAAAGUUAAAGAGCCUAUGUGUCUCUUGAGGCGGGGGUUAGAGGAUUCAAAUUUGGGAUGAUGCUCAUUGAUUCCUGACCAUAGCAGUGAGAGGCCAUUUUUUGUGCAGGAAAUGUGCUUAGGACUCAGUCUUGUUUUCGAUUAUCCACCACAGAAACCCUGAGACACAGAGCAGCUUAGAAGUCUCUACCCAGGCGUAAAUAGAGCUCCCUACUCCAGACCACCUGCCACCCACCUCCCAAGUUGAGAACACAAGCUCCAGCUGGGCUGGAGAGUCAGGCUUGGUGCAGGGUGACUUUGGCGAAGUUUUGUCAGAUCCAUAAAGCAAACUGGAAUUUGAGCUUUCACUUACCCUAGUAUACGUUCUUAAAAAAAAAAAAAAGUCUAUGUGGUAUAAUCGAGAUGGAUACCUGUGUCUUUAAAUUACGUAGGGAAUUUUGUAUGUUUAAAUAAUUGUACUGGGUUCCAUAAUGCUUAUCUUAGAAACUUUAGUAAAAGAAAAUAUAUGAACCGUGCAUUUGUGAAUGCCCCCCUUAGAGCAUUCAUCCAAGUUCAGUGUGUAGUGUGAUGGUUAUUAUAGAUAUUUAAAGUAUAGUAAGUGGCUGUGUAACAGGAGAGACUGCUGUUUACCUACGUACUGAAGGGUAACUGCUGCCCGCGUAAUUAAAUCAGUAUUGUCCUUUCCUGUCGGUUUGAUCAAUUGCGGUACCGGUAGCUUCCUGCUUGUGACUGUUACCUAAUUGUGUCAAUGUACAUCUGUAGUAUGUACAUGUGAAAGUGCCUUUCUAUUUUAGAGGAGUUUUAGCCUUGCUCUUGUACCGUUGCCCCGCUCUGUGCCCCACCCCCACCUCCUCCUCCCAAUUCCUGCUGCCCACUCGAGUGUUUCGAAGCUUCCUCCCUGUCCCCCACCUUCCCCAUCCCCGCCUUCCUGUGCCUCGGUGCUCAGUAAUGUCCCAUCUCACCUCCCUGUCGGUCCUCAGACUGUCUCGUUUUCCUUGUAGACGUGAUUGUGCCUUUCUCACCCCUGUGUCCUCCCAUCCCACCGCAUCAGUCCCCCGCUCAUGUGCUGCUGACAGCAUCGCAUUCGCCCGUGCUCUGUACUGCCUCUCACCAUUUCAUUCCCUCCUCUCUGAGGUGAAAAUAAAGGGGGAUGCUUUUACAGUCUGGAAAGAAAAAAAAUGUUUUGUUAAUCUGUUGUGACAAUGCACUUUUAUGUAUAGUACUGUACAUUUUUGGCAUGUACCAUUACAGGCUUCAGUAUACAGUCAGGUUUGUUCUUCACGGUGUAUCUUUAUAAUAAAUAAGAUAGUUCUGGCUGCCUUUGUCUGCUUCCAGUUUGAUGUGCAUCUCUGUGGUGUCUUUGUUCCUUUCCUUUCAUUCAUCACUACUUUCUCCUUGACAGCUAGCUUGCAUUAAAUAAUGUGAAACUUUUACCUUUAAAAUAUUUUUUUAUCUCACUUUCAUUUCUUGUUCAUUUGGAAAUAGGGUGUCCUGCACAGGGCCCUGCCCAUGAAGCUGUGGUUUUUCAGUCAUGGUUUGGAGGCUCAAUGUGUAGUCAGAGAAAAGAGUCUUGGCAGACACUUAACUGAGAAGCUGAGAGUGUACAAGCCUCCUAAACAUACACCAGAUUGAAAUCUUUCUUUUGAGAAAGACUCUAGUUAACCACGGCAAGCCCAUCUUUGGUUUCAUUUGAAUAAAUUGAAAAAUAAUCCUUAGGUUAUUUUUCUGUGCUUAGAACUCCCCGUGUAUUGGUAUUUUUCUUUACUUUUUUUUUUUUUUUUUUGAGACGAAUCUCUCUGUGUCACCCAGGCUGUAGUGCAGUGGUGCAAUCUCAGCUCACUGCAACCUCCCCCUCCUGGAUUCAAGCGAUUCUCCUGCCUCAGCCUCCUAAGUAGCUGUAAUUACAGGCACCCGCCACCACACCCAGCUACUUUUCGUAUUUUUAGUGGAAACGGGGUUUCACCAUGUUGGCCAGGCUGGUCUCAAACUCCUGACCUAAAGUGAUCUAUCUACCUGCCUCAGCCUCCCAAGUGCUGGGAUUACAGGUGUGAGCCAUUGCAUCUGGCCAGGUAUUUUUCUUUAAAUAUAAAAAAAAGAUAACUUGAGGUCUAGCAAUAUGUAGUAGAUAGCUUUGUAAAACAAUGUAAGUUGUGCAAGAUUGAAUAUUGAUAAGAUAUAAAGUUUAAAAAAUGACAGGCAAAUCAAGGAAAAACACUUUUUAUUAAAGUGCAGAAUACUAACAAAAGUGUGCAAAUCAUUAGUGUAACAGUUCUCACGAGCUGACACACUGAUGUAUCCACCACCCAGUUUAAGCAAUAGCACAUUAUCAGCAUCCCAGAAGCUACUGUGCUCAUGCCUCUGUGAAUGUAUCAGUAUCCUGACUAAUCACACCAUGGUGUAGUUUUGCCUGUCAUCUUAGCUUUCUAUAAAUGGGUUCAUACAGUAUGUAGAUUUUGUGUCUGGCUCCUUUUGUUGAAAUGUAUGUUUGUAAGAGUCGUCAUUGUUAGUAAAAUAGUGGUUUUUCCAUUUUUACUGCUAUAUAGAAUUCCAUUACAUGAAUAUGCUCAAUAUUAUAUUUAUUUUAGUAUUUCCUGAUUAAACUUUGGGUAGUAUAUGCAGAUAUCUUUAAACAUGGAGAAAUGAAUGGGGGGUGAGGGACCCACCUGUCAAAGGAAUUGUUUUCCCAAACUAUGACGGAAUAAUGUUGAACUAACCUGUUGACCGGAAGGCCUACUCAAAGGCAAGGAUACUUUUCUUUCUUUCCAAAAAAGCACUGUCUGAUAUGGAGACUGGAAAUAUUCAUAGAUGACACUGAAACUAGUUGAAGCUUUACUUGAUGCUUAUCAAGUCAUGUUCUCUUACCCGAUGCUGGAUGCUUUUUCUUCAAUGCCUACUUUAGGACCACAGAGUUGGAUUUAGAGGCUAGCCCACCAGGAACAAAUGCCCAAAUCAGUCUGUAGAGUUGUUCCAGGAAAGACUCCACCAUCCUGCUACCCUCAAAUCUUAAGCUCCUCAGCCUGCCACGACCAUCUCCUGUUGAGAAAAUUGCGCCUGCCUCCCCAUCUCUCACUCCCGAACCAGAGUCCCAACGGGGUGUAACUGGUCGUCAGUUCCCACAGUUCAUAUGCCUGCACCCUGUAAGAAUCUUAGAAAGGCAGAGCAAGGGUGUUUGCUGGCUUCUGCCUUGAGUAGUUGGGACUCCUAAAAAGGAAAAUUCCCCAAGUUUGACCUAGAAUGUCAAAAAGGUCCUAAAAGCACAGAAUGAUGGUAAAUUCUAUCCACAGGCCAUAUAGCCCUGGAAAAUAUUGGGAAACUGAGGCAUGGGUUGGUAAUUUAUUGAAGUUUAGUAAACGAAUUUGAAUUAAUUAGGACCAGAUAAUCAAUUUUUGGCUUACUUAUACUAUAGUAUAAGCAAAUAAGUAUUUAAACUUUAGUAUAAAUAUUUUUGCUCACUUAAUAAUCACGGUGAGGUUCAUCACCUCUUCAGUAGCCUUUUAUCUGUUUCUACAUAGUAAAUAGAAAACUUGCCUUCUAUAAUAAAAACAAAAUAGUUUUUCUAUCAAGGUCAGUCUCAGCAAGAGAAAUGGGACUGGGCUGGAUAUCAACACAUGUGCUUGUGUGCAUGUGCACGUGUGUGGGUGGGAGGGUGCGGAGGGGUUGGGAAGAGAGAUUGCUCCUCCCGCAGUGCUGAAACAACAUGCCUUGUUCAGUAUUAACAUCUUGAAGGCAGUUAUGGCAGCAUGAUCCAGGAGAUCGUCAGCUCUAGGAUAUUUGCGAUCCAAUUCUGGCGACUUAUGGAUGGAUCCUUCACACCCAACAGCUGUCUAUCAGGGGUGCUUCCGAGGGUCACUGGGUUUCUUUUAGCUGCUUGGCUGUGCAGCUGAAGUUAGGACUUUUGAUGAAUUACCCUCUCAAUGAUGGUGUAUUGUUCUAAUCUUCUGUCUCUGACAUACCCAAGGAACCCCUUGUGUAAAAAUCAUGUCCCUCUAAAUGCAAGUGGAUGAUUGUGCCAAUAAGCCAGGAGAGAAGGAAACAUCUUCAGUGGUCCAGUGGCACAUUCAAAAUUGUACAAUGACAUGACAUUAACUCAAAAAUGAAGUUUGAGGUUCUGGGCCUUUGAUGGACUGCAUCUAUUAAAAACAAAAAGUGGUGUCUCAUGCCUGUAAUCCCAGCACUUUGAGAGGCCAAGGCAGGAGGAUCAAAAAAUGCGAAUUUUUAUAUUUUUUUGUGAGAUCCCAUCUCUACCAAAAAAAAAAAAAAUACAAAAAUUAGCCAGACAUAGUAGUACAUGCCUAUAGUACUAGGUACUUGGGAGGCUGAGGCAGGAAGAUUGCUUGAGCCCAGAUGUUUGAGGCUGCAAUAAGCUAUGAUUGCACCACUGCACUCCAACCUGGGUGGAAGAGUGAGAAGCUAUCUCAAAAAAAAAAAAAAAAAAAAAAAAAACAUGGUCAAGAUUUGUAAUAGAAAUUGCCAUUUGAAUUUUGGUCUGUAAGCCCAAAGAUUGUUACUGUGUUAGUAACUAAAUAUUACGAGAUGCAUUAGGAAAAGAAGGAAAAGAAAUUUUAAGUAAGCCAAAAAUCUAUUAUAUAGUCAUAAGUCAAACUCAGUUACUAGACUUCAACAAAUACCAACCCAUGCCUCCAUUUCCCAAACAGAAAUAAUAAUAUGAACAUCUUAGUAUAUUGUCUUCUAAUCCUUACAUUAUGUUAUUUUUAAGCAGAGUCAAACUCAUAUUCUGUAUAUAAUUGUAUAUACAUUGGGUUUUUCUCCCUUAUAGCAAUUCACACUAGGAGUCUCAGUCAACAUGAUUUUUUAAUGGCUGUAUAAUAUUCUAGCGUAUGAACACAUCAUUAUUUAACCAUUUUCCUGUCACUGAGUGAGCCUGUUUGAAGGUUUUGUUUUUUUUUCAAUUGAAUGUUAUGUUGUGGUGAGCAGCUCUGUAUAUAAUAAUUAAUUGUCUGUGUUUGGAUCAUAAAGUUAGCAUUGACUCCAAAAAGUGAAAUCACUGGGUCAGAGGAUGCAAUUAUCUGUAAGGCUCAUGACAAAUAUUGCCGACCUGUUUUCCAGCAAAGUUGUACAAAUUUACAUCCCUGCCAGUAAUGCAUAACAGUACACGAGUAUAAAACAUGGUCAUGUUUCUUUACCAGUGUACUAGGUGAGUGAUAGGCUCAAUGCAAAUUCUUAGCAGUUUGUUAAUGUGCACACCCACAUUUCCAGAGUACAAAUCUCUAUUUCACUCACCUCUGUGUCCUAAACUUCAGAUGACUCUUUAUUGUUUCAGCUAAACAUCAGCAAACAGAGAUUUUCCUCAGGCACCUUAAGCUCAACAGACCCAAAAAUUAAACCCACUUUGUUUCAUUCCAAAAAAUAUUCUGCAGCCCCUCUACAUCCUCCAAUCUGUUCCGCUGCCUAUCUCUGCUCUAAGCUAAUUCUGUGCACCAUUCCCCUUGCCACAACGAUUGCCGUAGCUUCCACGGUGGUGUGGCUGUGCCCACUGUCUCCUCCUUGAAAUGAUUAUCUACACUGCUGCCAAUAAAUCAUCUUUCUCAAAAACAAAAUGAGAAACCUAACAAACAAUCAUUGAAAAUGUACCAUGUACUGACAUCGUUUUCCUCAACACGUUGCAUGUCAAUAGCCAACAUGUAUUGAGUACCAGACUCCAUGCUACAAAUGUUAACCCUCAUAAGAAAGCCAAGAGAGCCACAGUUAUUAUCAUCAUCUUUAUCCGUAAGAAAAUUAAGCCGCAGGAGUUAAACACUUGCCCUGGUCACACAGCUAGAUAGUGACAGAGCAGGAUUUGAUUCCACGCCAUCUGGUGCUGGAGGCUAUGCUCAUAACCACUGCUGCAUUCUGACCUCUGUAACAUGCUCAUGUCAUUACCCUGCUCAAAAGCCACACGUGGGUCCCCACUGCUGCAGGACGGCAUACUACUGUGUCUUAUUCAUCUUUGUAUCUUCAAGCCUAAUGCAUCACUAACUAAAUAGCAAAUCGGCGGAACUGAAAUGAAUUCAAUGUCUGCCGCUUUGACCUCAGCCUGCCAUUUCAGCCUUCCUGCUCACCACCUCCUCUUCGGAACCUUUAGUUUCAGCCAUAGCAAGCUACCUUUCUUUGAAAAUGUGAUGCUGUGUGCUCCCUCCGCAUAUACUUCAUGUCAUUCCUCAGCCUAAAAUGUCCCCUACUUCAUCCUGACAACUGCCUGUUGAAAUUAUAUUCAUCAUUCCAAACCCAACAAAAUGGUUACAUCCUUCAUGAAGGGUUCCCCAAACCUCCCAGCUGGCAUUAAUUGUUCUGUUACAUUUUGUUUUCAUUAAAUCAGGCUCCCUUCCGGGGAUCUAGCUGUGAAUGAGACACACAGGGCUCCUGGUCUCAUGGAGUGUACUUCCUGGUAUGAUUUAAAAAAAAAAAAAAAAAAAAAAAAACCACUACAUAAGCCAACAGCUAAACCGGCAAAAUAAUUUCAGGUGUUGAUAACUGCUACAAAAAGCAAAAGUGAAAUAAACAGGGUGAUAGAAUUUAGAGUGUCUAGGAGAAGCAUUUUAGAUGGGACAGCUUGAAUGCCACCUUGGAUGUGGUAGCAUUUGAGCUAAGACCUGAAUAAUGAGAAGGAACCAGCCAUGUGAAAAGGAAGAGAAAGACCCAAGCAGAAGGAACUGCACAUGGGAAAACAGGACCAUGCUCACGUGGUUAAAGAGUCAAACACAUUCACUGUGACUGUACCACCAUAAGCAAGAAGCCCUGGAGAUGAAAAUAAAGGCCAGAAUGUGGACAGAGAUCAGAUUUUGGAGGCCAAAGUAAGGUACUUAAAAUUAGCCGGGCUUGGUGGUGCACAACUGUAAUCCCACCUACUCGGGAGGCUGAAGCAGGGGAAUUGCUUGAACCCAUGAGACGGAGGUUGCAGUGACCCGAGAUUGUGCCACUGCACUACAGCCUGGGCGGCACAGUGAGACUCCAUCUCAAAAAAAAAAAAAAAAGUAAGGUACUUAGAUGUCAUUCUAAGUUCAAGGAAAGCCAUUGGAAGUUUCCAAAAAGGAACAUGACAGCAUCUAUAUUUUUAGAAGAUGACCCUCAAAACCACAAUGAGAUAUCACCUCAUACCCAUUAGGAUGGCCACUCUCAAAUGAUCAAACUCCAGAAAAUAACAAGUAUUGGCCAGGGUGUAGAGAAACUGACACCCUUGUGCACUGUUGGUGGGAAUGUAAAAUGGUAGAGCCACUAAGGAAAACAGUGUGGAAGUUCCUCAAAAAAUUAAAAAUAAAACCCUCAUAUGAUCCACCAAGCCCACUUCUGGGUACAUAUCCAAAAGAAUUGAAAACAGAAGAGAUAUUUGCACACUCAUGUUCACGCAGCUUAAUUCACAAUAGCCACAAGAGAGAAGCAACCCAUGAAUGGAUGAAUGGGUAAAGAAAAUGUGCCAUACACAUAAAAUAGAAUAUUAUGCAGCCUUAAAAAAGAAGGAAUUCCUGUCAUAUGCCACAAUAUGGAUGAAACUUAAGGAUACUAAGCUAAGUGAAAUGAGCCAAUCAAUAAAGGACAAACAUUGCAUGAUUUUACUUCUAUGAGAUAUCUAAAGUAGUCAAACUCUUAUAAACAGAAAGCAGAAUGGUGAUUGCCAGGGAUCGGGAUGAGGAAGAAAAUGGAAAUUGUUGUUCAGUGUUUACAGGGUUUCAGUUUUGCAAGAUAAAAAGUUCUAAAGAUCUGUUGUCCAACAAUAUGCAUGCAGAUAACAUCAUAUUAAACAUGGUUAAGAUAGUAAAUUUUAUACUAUGUAAUUUUUUAACCACAAUUUUAAACAUCACUGUAGAUGUUGUAGUUGUGUUUGGGGUCCACGGGUGGGGAGGAGCUUGGGAAGGAAUGGCAUGAGGGAAGUGAGAGACCACAAUUAAGGAGCAACACAGGAGAUGAGGGUGGCUUGGACUAGAUAGCCAGGUAGAAGGAGAGGAAGGGAUGAACCGGGGGUUCGUUUCAGAGUCAAAAUCAAGAUUUGCUAAUAAAUUAAAUAUGGGAAUAAAGAAAGAAAAGAAUCAAGAGUGGCUCCUAGUAUUUGUUUGAGCAAAUGGGUGGAAUAUAUUGAUAUAUACUUAAAAAGAAUGACUGGGGAAAGGAAGAAGUUGGCCAGGAUGUACAACCAAGUAUUCACGUUUGAAUUUAUUUAAUUUAAGAUAGGUAUUAGACUUCCAAGUGGAGAAGUCUAGGAGGCAGAUGGACUUGAAGCUCAGGGGAGGAUUUCUGGCCAGAAGGUGUAAAUUUGAUAUUUAAAGCUAUGGGACUCCCGGAAAGAGAAAGAGAAAGGAAGGUACAGAGCACAUAACCAAGCCCUGGGAAGCCCAGCUUGGGAGAGCUUGGGUGGAGUGAGGAGCUGGCAGAGGAGACAGAAGGAGCAGCCAGGGCGGAGGAGGAAAACCAGGAGGAGCAUGUAAUGUGAUCAGUACCCAGGGAAGAAAUGAUUGCCAUUUCUAGUGUGCAUUUGUUAACAUAAAUAUGAUAAUAAAAAUAGUUAACAUUUGUUAAAUAUAUAUAUUUUUUUCUUUUUCUUUUUCUUUUUUUUGAGACAGAGUCUCACUCUGUCACCCAGGCUGGAGUGCAGUGGCAUGAUCUUGGCUCACCGCAACCUCUGCCUCCCAGGCUCAAGUGAUCCUCCCACCUCAGCCUCCCAAGUACGAGGGAUUACAGGUGCAUGCAACCAUGCCCAGCUAGUUUUUGUAUUUUUUUGUAGAGACGGGGUUUCACCAUGUUGCUUGUUAAGGCCGGGCACGGUGGCUCACGCCUGUAAUGCCAGCACUUUGGGAGGCCGAGACAGGCGGAUCACCUGAGGUCAGGAGUUUGAGACCAGCCUGGCCAACAUGGCGAAACCCCAUCUCUACUAAAAAUACAAAAAAAUUAGCCGGGUGUGGUGGCGCCCGCCUAUAGUCCCAGCUGUUCGGGAGGCUGAGGCAGGAGAAUUGCUUGAACCAGGGAGGUGGAGGUUGCAGUGAGCCAAGGUCACGCCACGGCACUCCAGCUUGGGUGAUAGAGUGGGACUCCGUCUCAAAAUAAAUAAAUAAAUAAAUAUAUUAAAAAAUAAACAAGUUCAGGCUUGUUAAAUAUUUUUUAUGUUUGUUUGUUUGCUUUGUUUUUUUUGAGACGUAGUCCCGCUCCGUCUCCCAGGCUGGAGUGCAGUGGCGCGACCUCGGCUCACCACGACCUCGGCUCACCGCAACCUCUGCCUCCCGGUUUCAAGCGAUUCUCCUGCCUCAGCCUCCAGAGCAGCUGGGACUACAAGUGCGCACAACCACACCCAGCUAAUUUUUUUGUAUUUUUAGUACAGCCGGGGUUUCGCCAUGUUGGCCAGGCUGGUCUUGAACUCCUGACCUCAGGUGAUCCACCCGCCUCGGUCUCCCAAACUGUUGGCAUUACAGGCAUGAGCCACCACGCCUGGCUGAGUUAAAUAUUUUCUAUGUGCCAAGCACUGUGCUAACUGCUUUCAUAUUAUCGGAUUUAGUCCUGUAAGACCGGAAUCAUUAUUAUCCCCAUUUUUCAGAUUAAAACAAACAAACAAAAGCUGAGGUUUAAAGAAAUUAUCUCUUGUAAAAUCACACAGCUAACAAUUGAGCCAGUAUCUGGACCUAGAUCUAUUGCCUACAGAGCCGCACGUUUAACUACUGUUAUCUUGCCUCCUUAUUGCUCCACACACUUGAAAUAUAAAUUUUUAAAGACAUUUUAUUCUUUUUUGUCUUCAUCAGAAUUUAUUGAAUCCUGAUUAUUUUUUCCUUAAUGUUGAUUUUGUAGACUCAUUUGCAGGAAGAACAAUGUCAGGUGGAGAGAAGGAAUUGAAUGAAUAUUUUUAAUAAAUUUGUAGAUGUUAAUAUGAUUUACUUAUUUGCAAUUUUCAUAGCUAUAUGAUAUUCUAUCCCAUUUCCAGUGUUUUUGCUCUUUUAGUAGCAAAUACUCUGAAUCUCUGCAUAUGUUACUCAUUUUCUAUCAUCCUAUUCCUUGUGAUGGAUACCCAAGGGUACUCAUCUACAGGAUGAAAGGGUAUGAGCACGUUUCUAGGUGCCCUGACCCCAAGAUUAGGGGUUUUGUUAGAGGCAAAGCUAAAAGGAAAUGAUAAAAUAAAUGAAUAUUUAUAGAAGUUAAAUCUAUUAAUCUAGCCUUAUUACACCGAGUACAACAGGGAAUAAUAAGCCAUCUAUCUGAACGUGCACGGUUAGGGCCUCAAGGAAAGUGGGCUCAGCAAUGAGUGUUGGUACACAUGGAAAAUCACAUUUGCCAUGUUUUCUAUGGCUUUGGGCUGCUGCUGCAUCACUGCAGUUUAAUAGGAGGAGGCUGGUGAAAAUGUUACCAACUGCCAGGGGUCAAUGGCGAAAGAACACAUUUCUCUAGGAAAGAUUACCUUCUCUGAAGAAGUGAUAGGGGGAAUAAGGCAUAAAAUUAUCUGACCUGAGAGACCUUAACAGCUAGGCCUGCACUGCUCAUGCUUUGGGACCAGAAAGCGGAUGGUUUGAUAUGGUAGCUGCACUUCUAAAAAAAAAAGGGGGCAUUCUUGGCAGGAGAAAGGGUGUUACAUGGAAAGAUCAGCGAUAGUACACACGCCUUCCCAUAGAGUGAGGUGGCUUUCCCACCCCUCAACACUCCUUCAGACCCCCACUGUAACAAAGGGAUGUGUCUACCUCUAAAUUCAUCAUUUACUGAACAAAUAACUCAUGAGGGUUACCAUAUGUCUGACACUGUAGGAAGAGCUGAAGCAGGGCCUAAAACACUAUAGUGCAAGUAUCUGUUUACACAUCUGUAUGAGAGUAAUUGAUGCUAGCUGCUGUAACAAACAACCCCCCAAACUCAGUAACACAAUCAAGCUGUAUUUCUCCUUCACAUCAUAGCCUGGUGUGGGUCAGGUAGGUGACUCAGGGUUCUAGGCUCCUUCCAUUUUUUUGUCGCUGCCACACUGGAAAUGGGAUAGAAUAUCGUAUAGCUAUGAGAAUUGCAAAUAAGUAAAUUAUAUUAACAUGUACAAAUUUAUUAAAAAUACUCUUUCAAUUCCUUCUCUCUGCCUGACAUUGUUCUUCCUGGAAAUGAGUCUACAAAAUCAACAUUAAGGAAAAAAUGAUCAGGAUUCAAUAAAUUCUGGAUAGAAAAAAGAAUAAAAUGUCUUUAAAAAUUUAUAUUUCAAGUGUGUGGGGGCAAUAAAGAGGCCAGAUAAUAGUAGUUAAAUGUGGGGCUCUGUAGGCAAUAGAUCUAGGUCAGAUACUGGCUCAAUUGUUAGCUGUGUGAUUUCACAAGAGAUAACUGAUGCUAGCUGCUGUAACAAACAACCCCCCAAACUCAGUAACACAAUCAAGCUGAAUUUCUCCUUCACAUCACAACUUGGUGUGGAUCGGGCAGGUGACUCAGGGUUCUGGGCUCCUUCCAUUUUUUUUGUUGCUGCCACCUUAGUACGUGGCCACCAUGAAGAGGAAGAGAAAGCACUUGCAAUGAUGUGAGGUUUUCUGUCUUGGUAUGGAGGAGACAUGAAUCACUACUGUACAUGUCCAAGUCACAUGGCAAGGGAGGCCAGGAAAUGUCAUCUUCCUAUAAUGCAAGAAAAAGAACCCAGGGCCGGGCACAGUGGCUCACGCCUAUAAUCCCCACAAUUUGGGAGGCUGAGGCAAGAGGAUUGCUUGAGCCCAGAGCAAUUAAACACUGCCUGGUGCAUAGUUAGUGCUCAAGAAUUGUGCUAUAAUCAAUGUUACUAAAUUAUCUAGGAUUAGAUGUUUCUAAAUUAAAACUAUUUCCUGCUUUGUAUUUGUCCUUUAUUCCAAAAACUUAAAAAUUUCUCAUUUCUGGUUUGUCAGGGAUGAAAUACUAAAGCAACUUCAUGGAUUGUGAUUUCAAGUAUAUGAAAAGUUUAAGACCCAAUUGCUUUUGAAGGAGAUUCAUCUAGAAAAACCAGGGAUUCAAACCCAACACAUCGGGUGCUAAAGUCUACCCUCUUAGUUGACAUAGAAUUAAAUUAAAAUCAGUAUUGAUUGGAUUAUGCUUUGAUAAAAAUGUAACUUCAUUUAAGUCUAGUAAAUAAUUAGGAUUAUGAGGUCAGGAGUUUGAGACCAGCCUGGCCAAUAUGGUGAAACCCCGUCUCUACUAAUGAUACGAAAAUUAGCCGGGCAUGGUGGCGUGCACCUGUAGUCCCAGCUACUCGGGAGGCUGAGGCAGAAGUAUCACUUGAACCCGGGAGGUGGACGUUGCAGUGAGCCAAGAUCGCACCACUGCACUCCAGCCUGGGUGACAGGGUGAGACUCCAUCUUAAGAAGAAAAAAAAAGCAAUUACUUUUGCACCAACCUAAUAAAAAUGAAAAAUCCCAAUGAAAAUGCAUGAAUAUCAUGUGCCUUGACAACUUACGGAGCAUUUGGAACAUGUCAAACAGUAAUCAGAGGUCAGGUUGAGGAAAAAAUGAUAAGAACCCUCUCUGCCCCACCAUUCACAUCAUUCAGUGGAUCUAUGUACUAAAUCUAGCCAGUGGGUUGUGAGCAAAAAUGAUCUGUGUCACUUGUGGGUUAAAAUAUAAAAGAGUGCUAGGCACACUGGCUCGCACCUGUAAUCCCAGCACUUUGGGAGGCUAAGUGGGAGGAUCGCUUGAGCCUAGGAGUUCAAGACCAGCCUGGGCAACAUAGCAAGACCCCAUCCCUACAAAACAGUUUUUUAAAAAACUAGCUGUAGGGCAGGCACGGUGGUUCACACCUGUAAUCCCAGAACUUUAGAAGGCCGAGGUGGGUGGAUCACUUGAGGUCAGGAGUUCAGGACCAACCUGACCAACAUGGUGAAACCCCAUCUCUACUAAAAAUACAAAAUUAGCCAGGCGUGGUGGCGCAUGCCUGUAAUCCCAGCUACUCAGGAGGCUGAGGCAGGAGACUUGCUUUAACCCAGGAAGCGGAGGUUGCAGUGAGCCAAGAUUGCACCAUUGCACUCCAACCUGGGCAACAAAAGUGAAACUCCAUCUCAACAAACAAACAAACAAACAAACAGUAGCUGGUUGUGGUGGUGUGUGACUGUGAUCCCAGCUACUUGGGAGGCUGAAGUGAAAGGAUCGCUUGAGCCUGGGAGGUAGACGCUGCAGUGAGCUGAGAUCAUACCUCUGCACUUCAGCCUGGGUGACAGAGUGAGAUCCUGUCUCAAAAAAUAAUAACAAUAACGUAUGAGAGAGGAUUCAAGCUUUCCAAGCAGUCUCUUCCCCUGCCAUGGCACUCAUAGAAGCCUCCCGUUAAGAUGGCAGAGCUGUAAUGCUAGAAAAGCACAGACUGUUAAGUCACUGCAUGGAGGAUGGUCAUCCUGGAGAAUUGUUUGGACUCGAGUGGACUCUACAACAGCAGGAAAUAAACUACUGUUAUAUCAAGCUACUGACAUUGAGAAUUAGGUUGCAUAGUUAUGCCACAGCAUAAUGUAGCCUUUCCUGAUGCAUACAAUUACUUUUCCUUUCUUUUUUCUUUUCCCUGGAGUUCAUAAUUACCUUUGUUUCAUUUGCUUAGCUUUCUAUUUACAUAAAUAGGUAAAAAUUCCUUCUCAAAAAUCUUUUACAGAAGUGUUCUCAAACUCAAUGCAUUGAAACAUGCUAUAGUUUAUAAAUCUUGGAUCCAUCACUUAAAGAGGCAUUUGACCUGUUUCAGUAUGGAUAAGUUGUUCUCUAAGUCUACUGCAUAGCUGAGAGCCUAAGAUCUCUGGGGACUCACUCCACUUUUCUCUUGAGUUGGUUCCACUAUUUCCUGGAACCUCAUACAGCCAUCUCAGCUAGUCAUGACUGACCUAGAUUUAACACAGUAUAUCCUUAAUCAGCUUCCUGAUUGAGAGUGUAUUUUGAGACAUUCCAUGUCUAGAAAGUGUCUUUAUCUCACAUGUAAUUGUGAUAGUCUGGCUGAGUAUAAAAUCUUACUUAGGAUGUUAACUUAAAAUCAAUGUGGUCAAGGAAAGGAGGAAAAAUAUGUCCUCCUAGUAAUUCCCAGUGUAAGUGGAAAUGACCCAGCCCUAGAUUUACUUGGCUUUAGUUUCCAUCACCAUAGAUUUCUCAAUCAAAAGGCAAAUAUAUCUCAUAUGUCGGAAGAUUAAUGUAUGAAUAAUCAGUACCACUGGCAUAUGGCUACUCUCCUAUUUUCCUUACCCCUUUGUCUUCACAAGGAAGCCCAGACUCUGUUUGCCAGUGGCUGGGUCCUGGGGCCGAUAACUUCAAGCUAAACAUUCAAUAUCAGUAUGGUAGGUGAGGAAGAUUUUCUCAGAGUGGCUCAUUAUCUGGAAAGUGUAAGAAUGAGGUGGCAGAAAGAGGUAGAAACAGCAUGAAAAGGCAGAGCCAAGGAGAGAUCGACAAACAAGAAGGAUUGUGCCCAUAUUUCUCUAUUCUCUCUAGCAUUAUGAAUCAUUUCCCCUCAGGAUUUUGGAGAUGUUGCAUCAGUGUUGCUACCGAACAUUCCAAAGCCAUUCUAAUUCUGUUACUUUGUAUGUUCUUUUUUUUCCCUAUACAUAAUUUACUAUUGCAUGUUUUUCUCAGGGUUUCUGAAAUUUCAGAAUAUCCUGAUGUGGAUCUAUUUUGAUUCAUUGUACUGAAGACCAUUUCAGCCCAUCUUACACUUUGAUUCUGGAAAGUCUUCUUUUCCCUGGAGCUUAUAAUUACUUUUAUUUCAUUUGCUUAGCUUUCUAUGUACAUAAGUAGAUAAAAAUUAAUUCAUUCUCAAAAUCUUCCACAGAAAUGCUUUCAAACUCAAUGCAUUAAAAACAUGCUAUAGUUUAUAAACCUUCUUGGAUCUAUCAAGGAAGAUUUAUUUGAUUAUUUUAUCUCCUCCAUUCCAUCUGUUUUCUUAUAAUUCCUAAUAUUUGGAGGUUGGACCUCAUGAACUGAUCCUAUAAUUUUACUAAUUUUCCUCCAGUUUUUCAUCUAUUUGACUUUUUGCUCUAUUUUCAGGGAAAUAUCCUCAACUUUAUCUGCUAACUCUUCUGUUAAGUACUUUAUUUCUGCUCUCAUGCUUUUAAUUUCCAAAAGCUCUUUUUGUGAGCUGGCUGUUCAUUUUUUUAUAGAAUCCUGUCCUUAUUUGACAGGUCCUAUAUAUUUUUUUAUUUUGAGAUUAUUAGUGAUAGUUCUUCUAAGUUUUCUUCUCUCUGCACACUGUAUUUCCUCUAAGUUGCUUUUUUAAAUUUUUGACCUGUGUUUGCUUUGCUUUCGUUUAUGUUACAGGCUUUCCUAAAAUUCCUGGUGAUCCUUGGCUAUCUGCUCGAAUUUAAAAACAAGCACUAAAGAAGGGCACUAAAAAACAGAUUGUCAUAGCAGUAUUAUCCAUAAUAGCCAAAUGAUAGAAGCAAUGCAAAUGUCCAUCAACAGAGGGACAAAUGAAUAAGCAAAUGUGGUAUAUUGAUACAAUGGAAUACUAUUCUGUAAUGAAGAUGGGAAAGAACGGAGUACUGAUACACGCUACAACAUGGGUAAACUGAAAACAUUAUUACGUGAAAUAAGCCAGUCAUAAACCACAUAUUGUGUAUAUUUUAUCCAUAAGAAAUGUUCAGAAUAGGCAAAUCUAUAAAAAUACAAAGUAGAUUUGUAGUUGCUGAGGGCUGGGAAAAGGGUUUGGGGAGAGAAAUGACUGCUAAUGGGAGUAUGGGAUGUUCUUUUGGGGCUGAUAAAAUGUUCCAAAAUUCAUUGUGUGAUAACUACACAUCUGUAAAUAUACUAAAAACCACUGAAUUGUAUCCAAUAAAGUACUAAAUUGUAUGAUA